UGGAGGACCAUGAUGGUGGCGAGGAUGGGGAAAAUUGGCGAGGUUAAAAGAAGAGGAGUCAUCGACUGGGGCUGUAGGAAGAGUGACAGAGGGUGAGUUGGGUUUGGAGCGGGCAAGGAGGAUUUGGAAAGUAGAACAGGACUGGCAGAGAGAAGGGUGGCUAUGGAGAGUGAAGAAAGCCUGAACAUAAGGAAUCUCGGACCACUUCCCAUUGCAGUGGCAAAAGUUGUCUAAGUCUUUAAGGACAUUGAAAUCGAAAGUGCCAUUUUCGGGCCAUUGGGAGCUAUUGUCUAACCUGUAUUGAGGCCAGACAGUAUUACAGUAGAAAAGCAGCUUCUUAGGACAGACCUCUGAAUGGAGGCCGAGGGCAUUGAGGUUGCAUAGAAGACACCCAAGGGGGGUGGUCUUAGGAAGCGUAGAAUGAGAAGCUCCUAUGGUGAAUGGAGUGGGGCAGGCAGUGGAAGGAGAGACUGCCGGUCAACAAGGAUGGUGGGAGAGGGCGUCCUGUGUCCCGCAAGCCCUGUCUGGAAUAGAGGAGGUAGCCACUGAGACAGGCGUCCCUGAAAUGGAGGAACCGGAGGCCUGGAGGCCAGAGGAAGCCCUUGGCCCAGCGCUGGGUCUUUCGGGAAUUCAGAGACGGUCAAGGAUUCUGGGUCUUGUAGCUUCAAUGAGCAUGGCUACCACCUCUUCCAGGCUAUGCGGCUUGGGGUUGAGGAGAUAAACAACUCCACGGCCCUGCUGCCCAACAUCACCCUGGGGUACCAGCUGUAUGAUGUGUGUUCUGACUCUGCCAAUGUGUAUGCCACGCUGAGAGUGCUCUCCCUGCCAGGGCAACACCACAUAGAGCUCCAAGGAGACCUUCUCCACUAUUCCCCUACGGUGCUGGCAGUGAUUGGGCCUGACAGCACCAACCGUGCUGCCACCACAGCCGCCCUGCUGAGCCCUUUCCUGGUGCCCAUGAUUAGCUAUGCGGCCAGCAGCGAGACGCUCAGCGUGAAGCGGCAGUAUCCCUCUUUCCUGCGCACCAUCCCCAAUGACAAGUACCAGGUGGAGACCAUGGUGCUGCUGCUGCAGAAGUUCGGGUGGACCUGGAUCUCUCUGGUUGGCAGCAGUGACGACUAUGGGCAGCUAGGGGUGCAGGCACUGGAGAACCAGGCCACUGGUCAGGGGAUCUGCAUUGCUUUCAAGGACAUCAUGCCCUUCUCUGCCCAGGUGGGCGAUGAGAGGAUGCAGUGCCUCAUGCGCCACCUGGCCCAGGCCGGGGCCACCGUCGUGGUUGUUUUUUCCAGCCGGCAGUUGGCCAGGGUGUUUUUCGAGUCCGUGGUGCUGACCAACCUGACUGGCAAGGUGUGGGUCGCCUCAGAAGCCUGGGCCCUCUCCAGGCACAUCACUGGGGUGCCCGGGAUCCAGCGCAUUGGGAUGGUGCUGGGCGUGGCCAUCCAGAAGAGGGCUGUCCCUGGCCUGAAGGCGUUUGAAGAAGCCUAUGCCCGGGCAGACAAGAAGGCCCCUAGGCCUUGCCACAAGGGCUCCUGGUGCAGCAGCAAUCAGCUCUGCAGAGAAUGCCAAGCUUUCAUGGCACACACGAUGCCCAAGCUCAAAGCCUUCUCCAUGAGUUCUGCCUACAACGCAUACCGGGCUGUGUAUGCGGUGGCCCAUGGCCUCCACCAGCUCCUGGGCUGUGCCUCUGGAGCUUGUUCCAGGGGCCGAGUCUACCCCUGGCAGCUUUUGGAGCAGAUCCACAAGGUGCAUUUCCUUCUACACAAGGACACUGUGGCGUUUAAUGACAACAGAGAUCCCCUCAGUAGCUAUAACAUAAUUGCCUGGGACUGGAAUGGACCCAAGUGGACCUUCACGGUCCUCGGUUCCUCCACAUGGUCUCCAGUUCAGCUAAACAUAAAUGAGACCAAAAUCCAGUGGCACGGAAAGGACAACCAGGUGCCUAAGUCUGUGUGUUCCAGCGACUGUCUUGAAGGGCACCAGCGAGUGGUUACGGGUUUCCAUCACUGCUGCUUUGAGUGUGUGCCCUGUGGGGCUGGGACCUUCCUCAACAAGAGUGACCUCUACAGAUGCCAGCCUUGUGGGAAAGAAGAGUGGGCACCUGAGGGAAGCCAGACCUGCUUCCCGCGCACUGUGGUGUUUUUGGCUUUGCGUGAGCACACCUCUUGGGUGCUGCUGGCAGCUAACACGCUGCUGCUGCUGCUGCUGCUUGGGACUGCUGGCCUGUUUGCCUGGCACCUAGACACCCCUGUGGUGAGGUCAGCAGGGGGCCGCCUGUGCUUUCUUAUGCUGGGCUCCCUGGCAGCAGGUAGUGGCAGCCUCUAUGGCUUCUUUGGGGAACCCACAAGGCCUGCGUGCUUGCUACGCCAGGCCCUCUUUGCCCUUGGUUUCACCAUCUUCCUGUCCUGCCUGACAGUUCGCUCAUUCCAACUAAUCAUCAUCUUCAAGUUUUCCACCAAGGUACCUACAUUCUACCACGCCUGGGUCCAAAACCACGGUGCUGGCCUGUUUGUGAUGAUCAGCUCAGCGGCCCAGCUGCUUAUCUGUCUAACUUGGCUGGUGGUGUGGACCCCACUGCCUGCUAGGGAAUACCAGCGCUUCCCCCAUCUGGUGAUGCUUGAGUGCACAGAGACCAACUCCCUGGGCUUCAUACUGGCCUUCCUCUACAAUGGCCUCCUCUCCAUCAGUGCCUUUGCCUGCAGCUACCUGGGUAAGGACUUGCCAGAGAACUACAACGAGGCCAAAUGUGUCACCUUCAGCCUGCUCUUCAACUUCGUGUCCUGGAUCGCCUUCUUCACCACGGCCAGCGUCUACGACGGCAAGUACCUGCCUGCGGCCAACAUGAUGGCUGGGCUGAGCAGCCUGAGCAGCGGCUUCGGUGGGUAUUUUCUGCCUAAGUGCUACGUGAUCCUCUGCCGCCCAGACCUCAACAGCACAGAGCACUUCCAGGCCUCCAUUCAGGACUACACGAGGCGCUGCGGCUCCACCUGACCAGUGGGUCAGCAGGCACGGCUGGCAGCCUUCUCUGCCCUGAGGGUCGAAGGUCGAGCAGGCCGGGGGUGUCCGGGAGGUCUUUGGGCAUCGCGGUCUGGGGUUGGGACGUGUAAGCGCCUGGGAGAGCCUAGACCAGGCUCCGGGCUGCCAAUAAAGAAGUGAAAUGCG